AACACUGGAGGCUCUAAGAUGGCGGCAGUGGCAACCUGCGGUAGUGUUGCCGCGAGUACUGGGUCUGCAGUGGCGACAGCCAGCAAGAGCAACGUCACCAGUUUCCAGAGGAGGGGUCCUAGAGCCAGCGUGACCAACGACAGCGGCCCUCGACUGGUGUCCAUUGCGGGCACGCGACCGUCGGUGCGGAAUGGACAGCUGCUGGUAUCAACCGGGCUCCCAGCCCUAGACCAGCUCUUAGGUGGAGGUUUAGCCGUUGGAACAGUUCUUCUAAUUGAGGAGGAUAAAUAUAAUAUUUACUCACCUUUGCUCUUCAAGUAUUUCCUGGCAGAAGGAAUUGUCAAUGGGCAUACUUUGUUGGUUGCAUCUGCUAAAGAGGAUCCUGCCAACAUUUUACAGGAACUUCCAGCACCAUUACUUGAUGAUAAAUGUAAAAAGGAAUUUGAUGAAGAUGUAUACAAUCAUAAAACACCAGAAUCUAAUAUUAAGAUGAAAAUAGCUUGGCGUUACCAGUUAUUACCCAAGAUGGAGAUUGGACCAGUAUCAUCUUCAAGAUUUGGUCACUAUUAUGAUGCAUCAAAAAGAAUGCCACAAGAACUAAUUGAGGCUUCAAAUUGGCAUGGAUUUUUUCUUCCAGAGAAAAUAUCUUCAACUCUCAAAGUAGAACCCUGUUCUUUGACCCCUGGCUACACAAAGCUGCUUCAGUUUAUCCAGAACAUCAUUUAUGAGGAAGGAUUUGAUGGAUCCAAUCCUCAGAAAAAACAGAGAAACAUUUUAAGAAUAGGAAUUCAGAAUCUUGGCUCACCUUUAUGGGGAGACGAUAUUUGCUGUGCAGAAAAUGGUGGCAACAGUCACAGCCUUACCAAGUUCCUCUAUGUUCUCCGUGGUCUUCUGAGAACCUCUCUUUCAGCCUGCAUCAUCACAAUGCCAACACAUCUGAUCCAGAAUAAAGCCAUUAUUGCCCGUGUCACAACCUUGUCAGAUGUAGUAGUUGGUCUGGAAUCAUUUAUUGGUUCUGAGAGAGAAACUAACCCAUUGUAUAAGGAUUAUCAUGGAUUGAUUCAUAUACGGCAGAUUCCUCGGCUUAAUAACUUGAUCUGUGAUGAAUCAGAUGUCAAAGACUUAGCUUUUAAAUUAAAAAGGAAGCUAUUCACCAUUGAGGCUGGAGUGCAGUGGCACGAUCUCGGCUCACGGCAACCUCGCCUCCUGGGUUCAAGCAAUUCUCCCGCCUCAGCCUCCCUAGUAGCUGGGAUUACAGGCGCCCACCACCACACCCAGCUAAUUUUUGUAUUUUUAGUAGAGAUGGGGUUCCACCAUGUUGGCCAGGCUGGUCUCGAACUCCUGACCUCAGGUGAUUCAUCCGCCUCAGCCUCCCAAAGUGCUGGAAUUACAGGCAUGAGCUACCGCGCCCGGCCUAGGGCUUUGUAUUUCAAAGAGAACAAGUCUAAAGUGGGUGCAAGACAACUACUUGAGACAAGAGAGGAACAUUUAUCCUCCAGGCUUCUCAUACUUACUCAAGCAGAAAGACUCUGCAUGGGGAGAAGGUUCUUUACAGCAUUCCACAUUUUUAAUGAGCUUCCUUGCAAAGGCGACUGCAUUUGCCUCCAGACUUGUCAGACACAGUGAGCCGCUCAAGCAAAAUGGAUCUGGCAGAAUCCGCCAAGCGGCUGGGCCCAGGCUGUGGCAUGAUGGCCGGAGGCAAGAAGCACCUGGACUUCUAGGGAUUCCUCCUUAGUCGCUGCAUGCAGAAUUCUAUGACACUCUAAUUAUGAUUGCUAAUAGCUUAUGUAAAUAUUUUUCUUAACAAUUUGACCCUCCACUCCUUGAAAAACACAGGAUUAUAAAAUGGUGCCGCCAUUUCUCAUUUUUUAACUUUUUACAGAACUAGCACAGCAGAAAUACUUUUAAAUUUUUCCUUCAUGCUCUAGAGAAAAUAAUUUUAUUUUUAAAUAAACGCCAAAAAAUGUCAAAAUCUCAAGAUUCCUGACAGUGGUCAUUCGUGUGUGUACUAAGGCAUUUAGUGUCAUGGUAAAGUGCAUGUCACAGCAGGUAGCAUACAAAACAUGAUGAAAUUCAAGAUUGUAUGUGAAAACAUACUUUCUCUUUAUUACAGAAACAGUCACUUGCCACCAAAAAUGCUGUUUUUUAAAUGAAAAUGUGUUUACUAAUAUAUAAAAUAAAUUUGCAUUUAUGUAUCCAGUUAUUAAAUUGAUAAAGACAAAGUAAUAUUUUGGGAUUUAGAUUCCACUAGAGAUAAUUAGUCUACCAUAGUAGUUAUUAAAUAUAAAGAACUUCAGUGAUAGGAAACAUAGAAAAAAGAAGUGGAUGGUCUUUAGUUUAGUAAUCCUAAACAAUUGAAGUCAGUACUAUGAAAUUAUGUCAACAGGCAUCAUUCAGGAUUGAAAUUCAAACUGACAGCUACAUUAAUGCUAGGAUACCAGGAGAAAAACAUAUACUGAAGCUUGUUGAGAGAUUUUACAGAACAUAGGUCUGAGACAAAGUGAAAAAAUGAAACUAACUCAGAUUUCCAUUGCAUCACAUAAAUAUUUUGUUAAUAAUGAACAUUGGUUGAGUGUGUAAAUUUCUAACCAUGUAAACAUGUCUUUGGGGGGUAUAGCAUAUCGAACCAGUUUUCAUAUGAAACAUUAGGUGUUUUAAUUACAAUUCUAUAUUCUCAAAGCUUUUGACAGAUAAUGGAUAAAAAAUGAAAGUUGAAAAGUAACUUGCAUAUUUAAGAGUCUUGAUUUUUUAAAAGGUGUUUAACAUCCAUUGGGAGAAACUGAAUUUCCAAAAUACAUUUUCAAAUGUAUUUAAUAUUUUGAAGCAGUUAUAACUAGCAUUUUUAAGCAGCUUGCUUUUAAUAUACCACAAAUUAUACUUUAUUUGUUCUUGACAACAUUGUAGAAAACAAAGACUAGGUUUUUAAAACUGUCUAACCAAUAUGAUGAAUGUCAGUCACUUAAAAAAACCCACUGUAGCAUAAACACAUACUGUAUACAGCUUUUAUUCAGAAUUAGAAUAAUUGAAUCAAUGACAGUGAUUUGCCAGGAUGUCAAAUCUCUCCAUCAUAUCCUGUCACUACCAGUUUAUUUUUUGUGAUCAAAAUCAAAAAGACAACUAUUUUGUCACCCGCUAUUUCAUUAGUACUAAAAAUCAGGUUUCUUAUUCUAUUUUUUUAGAAUGUCGGGUUUAUUUUUUUCAUUUCUUUUAAUUCUAAAGACACAGAUUCUUCCCCAUUUUCUUUUCAAAAUAAAGUUUCAGAAUUGAUCUGUCAGUUAAAAUUAAAGGGCUUUAUAUUAAGCAAAGGUGCUUUUAAAUUUUAAAGCAACUUCAAAAAAUUGAUUUAGUCCAUAGAUAAUAAAUAAUGUUGUGCGGAUACUCCACAAAAGCUCUGCUAUGUCCUUUGAAAGCAUUAUGAACAUUCUGAAUAAAUUCAAAUGAGUAUUUUAGUCAGUUUAUUAUUUUAAUAACUCUAACCUUUUUCUUACCGUGUUGAUUCAUUUUAUACAACACACAAUGGAACAAUUACAUAGCAUUUGACUUGCUGAAAAAGAGAUACGAGGUCAUCAGAUAUGUAAAUUGCUUGUCAAAAUACUUAAUAGGUCAUUGAUAUACUUCCCUGGCUACCAUGUCUAUAAAAUUAACAGCCAAUUACUAGUUAAUAUAUGCUUUGCAAAUAGAUAACUACUAUAAAAAUUGAAUAUGCAUAUUUGAACCCUUAUUUUAAAUAUAAAAGAAACUUUUCAAACUCAGUAAAAGUGCAUUUUGAAUAAUAAGUGUACCUGGGCUUUCCAAAAAUCAUAUCCAAGUGCUUUGUUUUUCUAAUUCACUGGGCCGGCUUUGUAAAAAUAAGCUACUGGAGAGGGGUGUGUAUUUUUGUCUUCCUCUGAUAAAAACGCACUCUGAAAAUGUGUUUUCCUUUCUUCUGGAAACAUUAUUUGUUACUCAUUAUGUUAAUAACUUACUACAUAAACAUAUCUCUCUUCAAUAAUGCUACCUUAGGUAUAGACACCAUUUUGAUACAUUAUGAAAUAUACACUCCAUUAACAGAUUUUUUUUAAUUAUCAGCUUGACUCAAAGAUAUAAAUACUUAAGAACAAUGCCAAACGUAAUAUCUGAAAUGAUAUCUUUUAAGUGUUUCUAGUAUAUGAACUUCAAAACCCUAUAUGGUACUCAUUUCUUACACUAGAUUUGCCUUUCUUUAACAUGAGAUAAAUAUUUUGACUACUGCAGUUUGCUCAGGUGCUCGGGUUCUAAGACUUUUUGAAUUUCCUUUUAGUAGCCACCAUACAAUAUCUACUUUUCUCUUCCAUUUAUUCCUUAUGUCCACCUCCAGGAUCUUUAAAUACUAACAGUAGACAAAAUAAAACUACUUUAGAAGGAAGCGACACUCUGCAAUCAAUUCCCUGUCCAUCUUUUAACAAAUCAGACACACAUAGGCAUACAAAAGGAGAGUGGGGGGACCCCCCUAUUCAUUUGUUUAAGCCCAUUAUUAAUGUCAUUUCUAAGACAGCAUGUUACUGCUUUCCAAAGAUAGUCACCGUCAACAUUAUUGAAAUAAGCAGUACUAACCCUAAGUACUUACACUUUGAACUUUAAAACCGAGCAGUUGAGUCAUUCAGUACCAAGCCAAAACACAGAAAAACAAAAAAGCAGAUGAGGUUUAUUCUUGAGAAAUGAAAAAGAGAAGAAUAUAUAUUUCGCCUUGGUGAGCCAAACAUACAGAGAAGAAAAGGCUUUUUAAAAUCUUACUAGUAUGAGAGGCCCAGAGUAAAAAGAAAUAAGCAAAAGAAUAUAGACACAAUCCUAAGAUGACAUUCACAGAACAAAGCUGAAUCUUCAAAUAAUACUGUAUGAGUGAAUCUUAGGAAACCUAGUGAUGAUAGUAAGAAGAAAUGGCAGUGAGCUGUAGCAAGAAACCAGUUGUUCACCAUUUAAGGGUUAGGAGGCAUAGCUUUGGGGGAAAAAUAUUCUAGAAAUUCAUUGCAGUAAAAUGCAUUUUUUUACUUAGAGCAGUUUGAACGUUUAUUACUUAAAACAUUCAGCUCUUAUUCUAUUCACCUGGUUUUCCCAAGUCAGUCAAGUUUGGAGAAAAAAUUUAGACGUUUAGUCCUGGGAUUCUACUGAAGUCUUCACAAAUAAUCUCCAUCCUGGAAGAUGGUGUCAAAACAUCCCUGCAGAUACCCCAUUGAUAAAUAUAUAAAUAUAUGUAUCGUUAAAUAAAUAAUAAACAAAAAUUAUUUCAACAAUGAGUAAAAGGCCAACUCCCAGGCACUGCUACCACACAGAGCCUGCCAUGCUGUCCCCAAGAGAGUGCCUGGAGCUCUGUUUGGAAGGACAGCUCAUGUCCCUAGGGUGUGGGCAGAAGGCAAGGCAGCCGUUCCCAUCCUGCCGGACCAGAGGGCUUCUGCAGCUGAGCAGCCGCUUCUUCAGACUAUACCAGACUGUGCUACUUUGCCCUGGCAAUCCUGACCUUCAGAGCACACAUAUACGUGCCCAAGUGCACACAUACAGACCCUCCGCUCCCACGUCACUCCUUUUCUCCCAUUCCCACCUCUUGCACCUGGCGUGCGACAUCCGGGUCUCCAAAGUCUCUGCUGUCUACACAACAGAACCGUGGGCCGGAACUGGCUGCCUGACCGUGGUGGAAAUUACAGCCAGCGAGAAGGAAGAAGUAAGCCAGCCAGCAGCUGUGGCAUGCACUCCCACAUAGCCCUUCUCUGACAGUUCCCUCAGCACACAGCCCUCAGGGAAUGUAGGCUGCAAAAUGUCAGGAGGUAGAAAUGUCUGCACCGGCAAUUGUACCAACAGUGCGUAUGUGUGCUCACUCCCCUGCAGAAAUGUGCUGCUGUGCAGUGCAGGCUGACACUGAACAAAACUACAUGCACACAUACAAAAACUGCAACUUAGGAAGGUGUCUCCAAAUGUGCAGCAACUCUGGUGGAAUAAAAUUAUUAGUAUAUUUCAUGCCGGAGCAAUGAAUCUCAAUUAUCUGUUCACAAGUAAUUCCUUAACUAAAAAACAGUAGAUAUUGAACGAGAAGGUCAUGUUUAAAUCCUUCCAUUAAUUUCUACAUUUCUGAUCAUUUGCUUUUGGGGAUUUUUUUAAAGCAGAGUAUAAUUCAGUGGAAGUGUGUCUUUGUCCCCAGAGGUUUCUGCAUGUGCAAGCAUUUUAAUCUAGACUGCCAGAACCCCCAGGCUUUUUAGUGAAGUUUGCAGAGGAAGACUUAUCUGUAUUGACUUAUAUGUUGCACAGAACAAAUGAAAGUCUCAGACAGUCCUUUUUUACCCAACAAAGGCUUAUUUUUUUCCAUCCUUUGCUUGGGCUCAAGCACUCCUGCCCUGCGUGCCUCCACUUUAAACAUGAUCAGAACUGUGCUUCAUUGCAAAUAACAACUGACCAACAAUGGGCCCUGCUUCAUAGAUUUGGGAAUGUUUGGCUUAAGCUGCCAAUGACUGAAGGCCUUUAAUUCCCACCGGCCAGUCACAGUCUGCUUUGUUGUUGUCUGUUGAUGUGUCUGUGCUCAUUAUUCCUUGACAUGCAACAUCCCCCCUCCACCCUCCAACCAUCCACAACCGCACAGAAAGCAAGAUUCAAAUGGGAACAGCUGUAGUGGUUCAAUGGGAAAUGAUGCCUCUUGUGCAAAGGGGAGGGAGACAGAAAAGGGAGAGGGCCUAUUUGAAAAAGGCAACAGCUUUCAGAAAGUCUCCUUUAAGAAAUCUACUUUUGAAUAUACUUCAGUGAAAUCAUUGUUGAAAUAGGCUGACAAUGGAAAUCUGCCCAGAUUGAAAAUGCCAGUCCUAAUUCAAAAAACAAUUCCUAGCUAAUCGCUUGUUGCAUUUUUAAAUUAUUUCUAGACUUUGAGCUUUAGAAUUAAAUGGCUAACUGGGAAAUGUUACCAUUUUGUAUAUAUGUUGUGGGUAUAAAUGGGCACAGAUCUACACCCUGCUGUAAGUGGAAUUUUUUUCUAACACGUUUUUGAUUUAUGGUAUCUAUAAGGAUUAUUUUUUAAGGAUCAUCAGGAUGUAAAACAGAGUGUGUGUGAAAGUAACCAUUGGUUUAGAAUGUUGAUCUAACAUGGAAAUAAAAUUUGUAACACCACACUAUAAGGUUAAAAAGAAAACUGUAUAAUAAAGGAAAUACAAAGGCUUUGGCAUGGUUUUUUACAAUCAACAAUGGUUAAUUUUGAUAUGUAGUUGUGAACAACUUCAAAACACUUAAGUUUAAAACUCUUGCAAGCACUUUUAAUUGAUUAGGAAUGAACUCUAGAUGCACAAAAUGAUUGGACCGUGAACAGUAAUACAACUAUAUCUAAGAACAAUUAACUUUUGCUGGCCAAAAAAGAAACGUAUGAUUGCAUGAAAAUGUGUAUAAAACAUCUAUAUUCUUGUCAAAUAUAAAUGAAAUUAACUUUAUUAUAGAAAUCAUUCUGAGGAUUUCUAGGGAAGACAAAUACUUACAUUUUGACAUAAAACAAAUUGGAUUAUAUCGAAGACACACUCUACCUUUUAGCUAUCAACUUUUUUUCUUCCUUGAAUUUAUAUCUUACCCUUUUUUGCACAUAAACUUCAUCUGUUAACAACCUUUGGAAAACCAACAGAUAUUUCUGACAUAAAUCUAGUGCAUGUUGUUCCAGGUUUAAUUAUAUGCAAAGGAAUGAUACAAACUUGGAACAUCAGUCCAUAAACUAUGAACAGAUGGGUAGAAGUAUUCGAUAUAUCUUGAUAAAACUCUUAAAUUCGUGGCAAAGCUUGUUGAUCAUGGUUUUCUUUUUAAAAAAAAAAAAAACAACUUCAUGACCAACACAGAUCAAACAUCCAUCCAGUCUACAUUGUUCUUUUUUUCAUUAUAACAUACAAAUGCCCAUUUACAAAUAAUACACCAAAAUGAAUAAAAGUUUGGAUACCAAAAUGAAGAUUUGUUCCAACUGAUAUCGUGCCUUCUGUAUACAAAGGUCCUUGUUUCAAGUCCAUUCCUUCCCCAGUGGUACAAUACAGGACACAAUUGUAGAACUGAAGCGGCUCUAACAGCCAUUUUUCUUUCUUUCCUGAAAGCUCAACUGUUGUGUCCCCAUAGUCACUGACUGAAUUAACACAAUAUUUCCUUUCCUUUUUUUUUUUUUUUUUUUUUUUACUGUAAUCUUGGCCAGUAUUGAGACAUAUCAGGUUCACUUCCGGGAACUUGAACUGGAACUGACACACCAGGGGAAAUGAGUCCUAGAAGUGGAUGAAAGAAAUAGCCAUGUAGAUAUUCCCUUUGAGAAACAGACAUGGAAUACAAAUUUAUAGGUUUACAAAAAAAAAAAAAAAAAAAAAAACUAAUACUUUCUAACAUUUUUUACUGUAUUAAAAUCACUUCAAUUGUUACAAAUAAAAGUAGCACCUUCAGAAACUAGACAAUAUAUGUAUAUAUACCUAUUGGAUCCCAAGUACCCCCCACCCCAAUCCAAAGGAAAAGAAAAAAAAAAUCCUCUGUUUGUUUGCAUGUUUGGAACUUUUACAAUAAAGCUGUCUCUGGAAAA